AGAUAAGGGCACUGAGGCUGAGAGAGGAGCUGAAACCUACCCGGGGUCACCACACACAGGUGGCAAGGCUGGGACCAGAAACCAGGACUGUUGACUGCAGCCCGGUAUUCAUUCUUUCCAUAGCCCACAGGGCUGUCAAAGACCCCAGGGCCUAGUCAGAGGCUCCUCCUUCCUGGAGAGUUCCUGGCACAGAAGUUGAAGCUCAGCACAGCCCCCUAACCCCCAACUCUCUCUGCAAGGCCUCAGGGGUCAGAACACUGGUGGAGCAGAUCCUUUAGCCUCUGGAUUUUAGGGCCAUGGUAGAGGGGGUGUUGCCCUAAAUUCCAGCCCUGGUCUCAGCCCAACACCCUCCAAGAAGAAAUUAGAGGGGCCAUGGCCAGGCUGUGCUAGCCGUUGCUUCUGAGCAGAUUACAAGAAGGGACUAAGACAAGGACUCCUUUGUGGAGGUCCUGGCUUAGGGAGUCAAGUGACGGCGGCUCAGCACUCACGUGGGCAGUGCCAGCCUCUAAGAGUGGGCAGGGGCACUGGCCACAGAGUCCCAGGGAGUCCCACCAGCCUAGUCGCCAGACCUUCUGUGGGAUCAUCGGACCCACCUGGAACCCCACCUGACCCAAGCCCACCUGCUGCAGCCCACUGCCUGGCCAUGACCAUCACUUACACAAGCCAAGUGGCUAAUGCCCGCUUAGGCUCCUUCUCCCGCCUGCUGCUGUGCUGGCGGGGCAGCAUCUACAAGCUGCUAUAUGGCGAGUUCUUAAUCUUCCUGCUCUGCUACUACAUCAUCCGCUUUAUUUAUAGGCUGGCCCUCACGGAAGAACAACAGCUGAUGUUUGAGAAACUGACUCUGUAUUGCGACAGCUACAUCCAGCUCAUCCCCAUUUCCUUCGUGCUGGGCUUCUACGUGACGCUGGUCGUGACCCGCUGGUGGAACCAGUACGAGAACCUGCCGUGGCCCGACCGCCUCAUGAGCCUGGUGUCGGGCUUCGUCGAAGGCAAGGACGAGCAAGGCCGGCUGCUGCGGCGCACGCUCAUCCGCUACGCCAACCUGGGCAACGUGCUCAUCCUGCGCAGCGUCAGCACCGCAGUCUACAAGCGCUUCCCCAGCGCCCAGCACCUGGUGCAAGCAGGCUUUAUGACUCCGGCAGAACACAAGCAGUUGGAGAAACUGAGCCUACCACACAACAUGUUCUGGGUGCCCUGGGUGUGGUUUGCCAACCUGUCAAUGAAGGCGUGGCUUGGAGGUCGAAUCCGGGACCCUAUCCUGCUCCAGAGCCUGCUGAACGAGAUGAACACCUUGCGUACUCAGUGUGGACACCUGUAUGCCUACGACUGGAUUAGUAUCCCACUGGUGUAUACACAGGUGGUGACUGUGGCGGUGUACAGCUUCUUCCUGACUUGUCUAGUUGGGCGGCAGUUUCUGAACCCAGCCAAGGCCUACCCUGGCCAUGAGCUGGACCUCGUUGUGCCCGUCUUCACGUUCCUGCAGUUCUUCUUCUAUGUUGGCUGGCUGAAGGUGGCAGAGCAGCUCAUCAACCCCUUUGGAGAGGAUGAUGAUGAUUUUGAGACCAACUGGAUUGUCGACAGGAAUUUGCAGGUGUCCCUGUUGGCUGUGGAUGAGAUGCACCAGGACCUGCCUCGGAUGGAGCCGGACAUGUACUGGAAUAAGCCCGAGCCACAGCCCCCCUACACAGCUGCUUCCGCCCAGUUCCGUCGAGCCUCCUUUAUGGGCUCCACCUUCAACAUCAGCCUGAACAAAGAGGAGAUGGAGUUCCAGCCCAAUCAGGAGGACGAGGAGGAUGCUCACGCUGGCAUCAUUGGCCGCUUCCUAGGCCUGCAGUCCCAUGAUCACCAUCCUCCCAGGGCAAACUCAAGGACCAAACUACUGUGGCCCAAGAGGGAAUCCCUUCUCCACGAGGGCCUGCCCAAAAACCACAAGGCAGCCAAACAGAACGUUAGGGGCCAGGAAGACAACAAGGCCUGGAAGCUUAAGGCUGUGGACGCCUUCAAGUCUGCCCCACUGUAUCAGAGGCCAGGCUACUACAGUGCCCCACAGACGCCCCUCAGCCCCACUCCCAUGUUCUUCCCCCUAGAACCAUCAGCGCCGUCAAAGCUUCACAGUGUCACAGGCAUAGACACCAAAGACAAAAGCUUAAAGACUGUGAGUUCUGGGGCCAAGAAAAGUUUUGAAUUGCUCUCAGAGAGCGAUGGGGCCUUGAUGGAGCACCCAGAAGUAUCUCAAGUGAGGAGGAAAACUGUGGAGUUUAACCUGACGGAUAUGCCAGAGAUCCCCGAAAAUCACCUCAAAGAACCUUUGGAACAAUCACCAACCAACAUACACACUACACUCAAAGAUCACAUGGAUCCUUAUUGGGCCUUGGAAAACAGGUCUGUCCUCCACCUGAACCAGGGGCACUGCAUUGCCCUGUGCCCCACCCCAGCUUCCCUUGCUCUGAGCCUACCCUUCCUCCACAAUUUCCUAGGGUUCCAUCACUGCCAGAGCACACUGGACCUACGCCCAGCACUGGCUUGGGGUAUAUACUUGGCCACCUUCACAGGGAUCCUAGGGAAGUGUUCGGGACCUUUUCUCACUUCACCCUGGUAUCACCCGGAAGACUUCUUGGGACCAGGUGAAGGAAGAUGAGGUUGUGCUGACCAGAAUGCUGCUGGAGAACUGCCCCAGGGCUGACAGGCCAGGCUUAGCUGAGCAGAUGUUAUCACUGGCCCCAACUUACUUUGAGCAAGGGUGGCUGACCCAAAACCAUGAGGUGGCAGUCAGCUGGAUGACAGAUGAACACUUCCCCCAUAACUAUUUAGGGUAGUACCCAAGCACUACAGGAAAGGGUGGCAGGAACUGCCUCACUCCUAGGAACUGGUAGAUGGUGAGGUUGAGGGUGUCCAGCGCCCUUAGGUCAUUUUCUCACUGCCUGGGAACCUCACCAAAAUACUUCUUGCUUCCUUGGGGUCAGCCCAAAGCUGUCACAAAAUCAGAUAUUUCCCUUUAUUCCAGAUUUCCUGGACACUUUCACCCAAUUAUAAACACCCCACUUCAGCCCCAAUCACGUGGGAGGAAGUGUAACUUCCCUUUUCUGGAUUCUCAAGCAGUUACUUUCACGGUCAGAACACGCAGCUAUUAUGAUUGAAAACUUAAAAGGGCAACAAUUUCAGUCUUGCUUCUAGGGCUAGACAGGAACUUGGCAAACAUCUGUGGCCUGUUCAGCAAAGGAUGUUAAUAUUUAAGAAUCUUGUCUUGGGCUGGGUGUGGAGGCAAGUGGAUCACAGGAGGUCAGGAGUUUGAGACCAACCUGGCCAACAUGAUGAAACCCCAUCUCUACCAAAAAAAAUACAAAUCAGCUGGGCGUCGUGGUGUGCCUGUAGUCCCAACGCAGGAGGUUGAGGGGAGAAUUGCUUGAACCCAGGAGGUGGUGGUUGCAGUGAGAUUGAGCAACUGCAAUCCAGCCUGGGCGACGGAGUGAGACUGUCUCAAAAAAAAAAAAAAAAGGAUCGUCUCAACCUUUGCCCUCCUACUGCAACAUUUUGGUAUUUGAAAUGAAGGGACCUUCCAUACUUAUGCUGUUAAUACUUUCAUUCUCACUAGGGAUGAAGCACAUUCCUAACCUGCUUCCUAAUGGGGAUGCUUCGCCAGCCAGGUCCUCACCUGUGUGUACACCAGCAGGACACUGAUCCAGUCACAGCCAUACAGCUGUCCACACUGAAGAACAUGUCCUACAACAGCCUGAAUCAAAUGGUUAGCUUAAUAGAUAAAAAUCCCAGACUACUUCAGCCUUUAAUGCCUUUUAUUCAUAAAAACUGUGAAAGCUAGACUGAACCAUUGGAAACAUUUAACUCAGACUCUGGAUUCAGAGUCGGGAACCCUUAGUUCUAUCUGAAUCCAAGACAGCCACACCUUAGUAUACUGCCCAAACUAAUGAGUUUAAUAAAUACAAAUACUCGUUUCUUUUUGAUUAGUGUGAUUAGAACUGAACAACGGCACUUAAGGAAUCUGGAAGAUAGCCUGGAUAGAUUUCUGAUUCAUCCCAAGACCUCAAAGACAACACCUGGGUACCAAAUUUCUUUAUUUGAAGGAAUGGUACAAAUCAAAGAACUUAAGUGGAUGUUUUGGUACAACUUAUAGAAAAGGUAAAGGAAACCCCAACAUGCAUGCACUGCCUUGGUGACCAGGGAAGUCACCCCACGGCUAUGGGGAAAUUAGCCCGAGGCUUAGCUUUCAUUAUCACUGUCUCCCAGGGUGUGCUUGUCAAAGAGAUAUUCCGCCAAGCCAGAUUCGGGCGCUCCCAUCUUGCGCAAGUUGGUCACGUGGUCACCCAAUUCUUUGAUGGCUUUCACCUGCUCAUUCAGGUAAUGUGUCUCAAUGAAGUCACACAACUGCAAAACAAUGGGGAAGACAGUUAGUGGGCAGCUUUCCCAAUCCCUAAGGCAAAUGAUUUCCUCCAUUUAUUUCCUGGGGUUCCAAUACUCACAUGGGGGUCAUUUUUGUCAGUGGCCAGUUUGUGCAGUUCCAGUAGUGACUGAUUCACAUUUUUUUCCAAAUGUAAUGCACACUCCAUUGCAUUCAGCCCGCUCUCCCAGUCAUCACAGUCUGGUUUCUGAAUGAGAAUAGGUUAAUGCAUCUCUACCAACUAACCUAGAAGUCAGCAAGCCCAUCAUCUCUAACCACCACGUUUUGGCAAAAGGGACAUUACUAUUUGCCUAAUUUAGUUUAGAUGGUAAGCCUAAAAAAGCACAAAAGGCAAAAGCCCAGUGUAUCAUCACUUUAUAAGGGCAAUUGCUAGUUUAAGUGAUUUCUGAUACCCGAACACUGCCAGAUGAUGAAGUAUGACACCCCUAGGAUCUUUUGUUCACCUUGAUAUCCUGAAGGAAGAUUCGGCCACCUCGUUGGUUCUGCAGCUUCAUCAGUUUCUCAGCAUGUUCCCUCUCCUCAUGAGAUUGGUGAAGAAAGUAUUUGGCAAAGUUCUUCAAAGCCACAUCAUCGCGGUCAAAGUAGUAAGA